GUCGCUGACGUGGAGGCGUCCGAAGGGCAGCAGGGUGUGUCGGGGCUCGGAUUAAGACAUCGGAGUCGGAGACCUGAGAGAUGUUAACCAAAUUCGAGACCAAGAGCGCGCGGGUCAAAGGGCUCAGCUUUCACCCCAAAAGACCUUGGAUCCUGACUAGUUUACAUAAUGGGGUCAUCCAGUUAUGGGACUAUCGGAUGUGCACUCUCAUUGACAAGUUUGAUGAACAUGAUGGUCCAGUGCGAGGCAUUGACUUCCAUAAGCAGCAGCCACUGUUCGUCUCUGGAGGAGAUGACUAUAAGAUUAAGGUUUGGAAUUACAAGCUUCGGCGCUGUCUUUUCACAUUGCUUGGGCACUUAGAUUAUAUUCGCACCACGUUUUUUCAUCAUGAAUAUCCCUGGAUUCUGAGUGCCUCCGAUGAUCAGACCAUCCGAGUGUGGAACUGGCAAUCUAGAACCUGUGUUUGUGUGUUAACAGGGCACAACCAUUAUGUGAUGUGUGCUCAGUUCCACCCCACAGAAGACUUGGUAGUAUCAGCCAGCCUGGACCAGACUGUGCGCGUUUGGGAUAUUUCUGGUCUGAGGAAAAAAAACCUGUCCCCUGGUGCGGUGGAAUCGGAUGUGAGAGGAAUAACUGGGGUUGAUCUAUUUGGAACUACAGAUGCAGUGGUGAAGCAUGUACUAGAGGGUCACGAUCGUGGAGUAAACUGGGCUGCCUUCCACCCCACUAUGCCCCUUAUUGUAUCUGGGGCAGAUGAUCGUCAAGUGAAGAUCUGGCGCAUGAAUGAAUCAAAGGCAUGGGAGGUUGAUACCUGCCGGGGCCAUUACAACAAUGUAUCUUGUGCCGUCUUCCACCCUCGCCAAGAGUUGAUCCUCAGCAAUUCUGAGGACAAGAGUAUUCGAGUCUGGGAUAUGUCUAAGCGGACUGGGGUUCAGACUUUCCGCAGAGACCAUGAUCGUUUCUGGGUCCUAGCUGCUCACCCUAACCUUAACCUCUUUGCAGCAGGCCAUGAUGGUGGUAUGAUUGUGUUUAAGCUGGAACGGGAACGGCCAGCCUAUGCUGUUCAUGGCAAUAUGCUACACUAUGUCAAGGACCGAUUCUUACGACAGCUGGAUUUCAACAGCUCCAAAGAUGUAGCUGUGAUGCAGUUGCGGAGUGGUUCCAAGUUUCCAGUAUUCAAUAUGUCAUACAAUCCAGCAGAAAAUGCAGUCCUGCUUUGUACAAGAGCUAGCAAUCUAGAGAAUAGUACCUAUGACCUGUACACCAUCCCUAAAGAUGCUGACUCCCAGAAUCCUGAUGCGCCUGAAGGGAAACGAUCCUCAGGCCUGACAGCCGUUUGGGUCGCUCGAAAUCGGUUUGCUGUCCUAGAUCGGAUGCAUUCGCUUCUGAUCAAGAAUCUGAAGAAUGAGAUCACCAAAAAGGUACAGGUGCCCAACUGUGAUGAGAUCUUCUAUGCUGGCACAGGCAAUCUCCUGCUUCGAGAUGCGGACUCUAUCACACUCUUUGACGUACAGCAGAAGCGGACUCUGGCAUCUGUGAAGAUUUCUAAAGUGAAAUACGUUAUCUGGUCAGCAGACAUGUCACAUGUAGCACUACUAGCCAAACACGAACACUCAUGCCCUUUGCCUCUUACAGCCAUUGUGAUCUGUAACCGCAAACUGGAUGCUUUAUGUAACAUUCAUGAGAACAUUCGUGUCAAGAGUGGGGCCUGGGAUGAGAGUGGGGUAUUUAUCUAUACCACAAGCAACCACAUCAAAUAUGCUGUCACCACUGGGGACCACGGGAUCAUUCGAACUCUGGAUUUACCCAUCUAUGUCACACGGGUGAAGGGCAACAAUGUAUACUGCCUAGACAGGGAGUGUCGUCCCCGGGUACUCACCAUUGAUCCCACUGAGUUCAAAUUCAAGCUGGCCCUGAUCAACAGAAAAUAUGAUGAGGUACUGCACAUGGUGAGGAAUGCCAAACUAGUUGGCCAGUCUAUUAUUGCUUAUCUCCAGAAGAAGGGCUAUCCUGAAGUGGCACUGCAUUUUGUCAAGGAUGAGAAAACUCGCUUUAGUCUGGCACUGGAGUGUGGAAACAUUGAGAUUGCUCUGGAAGCAGCCAAAGCACUGGAUGACAAGAACUGCUGGGAAAAGCUGGGAGAAGUGGCCCUGCUGCAGGGGAACCACCAGAUUGUGGAAAUGUGCUAUCAGCGUACCAAAAACUUUGACAAACUUUCCUUCCUGUAUCUUAUCACUGGCAACUUAGAAAAACUUCGCAAGAUGAUGAAGAUUGCUGAGAUCAGAAAGGACAUGAGUGGCCACUAUCAGAAUGCCCUAUACCUGGGUGAUGUGUCAGAGCGUGUGCGGAUCCUGAAGAACUGUGGACAGAAGUCCCUGGCCUAUCUCACAGCUGCUACCCAUGGCUUAGAUGAAGAAGCUGAGAGCCUAAAGGAGACAUUUGACCCAGAGAAGGAGACAAUCCCAGACAUUGACCCUAAUGCCAAGCUGCUCCAGCCACCUGCACCUAUCAUGCCAUUGGAUACCAAUUGGCCUUUAUUGACUGUAUCCAAAGGAUUUUUUGAAGGCACCAUUGCCAGCAAAGGGAAGGGAGGAGCACUGGCUGCUGACAUUGACAUUGACACUGUUGGUACAGAGGGCUGGGGAGAGGAUGCAGAGCUGCAGUUGGAUGAAGAUGGGUUUGUGGAGGCUACAGAAGGUUUGGGGGAUGAUGCUCUUGGCAAGGGACAGGAAGAAGGAGGUGGCUGGGAUGUAGAAGAAGAUCUGGAGCUCCCUCCUGAGCUGGAUAUAUCCCCUGGGGCAGCUGGUGGGGCUGAAGAUGGUUUCUUUGUGCCCCCAACCAAGGGAACAAGUCCAACUCAGAUCUGGUGUAAUAACUCUCAGCUUCCAGUUGAUCACAUCCUGGCAGGCUCUUUCGAAACAGCCAUGCGGCUCCUUCAUGACCAAGUAGGGGUAAUCCAGUUUGGCCCCUACAAGCAACUGUUCCUACAGACAUACGCCCGAGGCCGCACAACCUAUCAGGCUCUGCCCUGCCUACCCUCCAUGUAUGGCUAUCCUAAUCGCAACUGGAAGGAUGCAGGGCUGAAGAAUGGUGUACCAGCUGUGGGCCUGAAGCUUAAUGACCUCAUCCAACGGUUGCAGCUGUGCUACCAGCUCACCACAGUUGGCAAAUUUGAGGAGGCUGUGGAAAAAUUCCGUUCCAUCCUUCUCAGUGUGCCACUUCUUGUUGUGGACAAUAAACAAGAGAUUGCAGAGGCCCAGCAGCUCAUCACCAUUUGCCGUGAGUACAUUGUGGGUUUGUCCGUGGAGACAGAAAGGAAGAAGCUGCCCAAAGAGACUCUAGAACAGCAGAAGCGCAUCUGUGAGAUGGCAGCCUAUUUCACCCACUCAAACCUGCAGCCUGUGCACAUGAUCCUGGUGCUGCGUACAGCCCUCAAUCUGUUCUUCAAGCUCAAGAACUUCAAGACAGCUGCCACCUUUGCUCGGCGCCUACUAGAACUCGGGCCCAAGCCUGAGGUGGCCCAACAGACCCGAAAAAUCCUGUCUGCCUGUGAGAAGAAUCCCACAGAUGCCUACCAGCUCAAUUAUGACAUGCACAACCCCUUUGACAUUUGUGCUGCAUCAUAUCGGCCCAUCUACCGUGGAAAGCCAGUAGAAAAGUGUCCACUCAGUGGGGCCUGCUAUUCCCCUGAGUUCAAAGGUCAAAUCUGCAGGGUCACCACAGUGACAGAGAUUGGCAAAGAUGUGAUUGGUUUAAGGAUCAGUCCUCUGCAGUUUCGCUAAGGCCCCCUUUGUGUGCAUGGGUCAGUCACCAUAUGUUCCCCCCAGAGAAUGUGUCUAUAUCCUCCUUCUAACAGCACCUUCCCCCUGCAGCUACUCUUCAGAUCUGGCUCUCUGUACCCUAAAACCUAGUAUCUUUUUCUCUUCUAUGGAAAAUCCGAAGGUCUAAACUUGACUUUUUUGAGGUCUUCUCAACUUGACUACAGUUGUGCUCAUAAUUGUCCUUGCCUUUCCAGCUUAAUUAUUUUAAGGAACAAAUGAAAACUCUGGGCUGGGUGGAGUGGCUCAUACCUGUAAUCCCAGCACUUUGGGAGGCUACGGUGGGCAGAUCAUCUGAGGCCAGGAGUUCGAGACCUGCCUGGCCAACAUGGCAACACCCCGUCUCUAAUAAAAAUAUAAAAAUUAGCCUGGCAUGGUAGCAUGCGCCUAUAGUCCCAGCUGCUCAGGAGGCUGAGGCAUGAGAAUCGCUUGAACCUAGGAGGUGGAGGUUGCAUUCAACUGAGAUCAUACCACUUCAUUCCAGCCUGGGUGACAGAGCAAGACUCUGUCUCAAAAAAAAAAAAAAGGAAAACUCUGUGAUGGACAUUUGUUUAGUAAAUCCCUUCAGUAUUUAUCCCUCCUUUCCCCACAGCAGCUUUCUUUCCUGUCAACUAGAAAGGAGCAGGAUGUAAUAAAUACAUUUUGGUGUGACUAGGCCACACCAACUCUUAAUCAUCUCCCAUUUUCCUUAGACAUUUAAAUUUCAAGGCAGGUACCCUCUGUGUACUCAGAAAUUUGAAGAAGUUAUUUGGUUUUCCAAAAUGCACACUGCGGGUUAUUGAUUUGUUCUUUACAACUAUUGUUCUCAUAUUUCUCACACUAAAUAAAUCUCUAUGAGAGCUUCUUGACUUGGCCAUUUAUUUCUUGGACACUCUCAUGUUCUUGUUCACCCAUGCAGGCACCCCACCAAAGUACAUAUCUUCCUUCCAGUAAUAAUUUUUAAUUACAAAAUAAACAUCCACUAUUGGAAAAAAAAAAAAAAAGCUAGCCGGGCAUGGUGGUGGGUGCCUGUAAUCCCAGCUACUCUGGAGGCUGAGGCAGAGGAUUGCUUGAACCCGGGAGGCGGAGGUUGCAGUAAGCUGAGAUCGCGCCACCGCACUCCAGCCUGGGCGACAGAGUGAGACUCCAUCUCAAAAAAAAAGAAAGAAAAAAAGAAGCACAUGUUUUUCAUAGGGUAUAUAUGAGGACCUAAACUGCUGUGAAAAUGAUAGAAAGCAAGUAGCUCCCUUAUUCUGUUUUUGAUUGCAGCCUUUUAUCUUUUGCUAAUUAUAGCAAUAUUUAUUGAGCACCUGCCAUGUGACUGUCACUGUUCUAGAUAUUUUACAUGUAAUAUACAGAUAAAAGAAUAGUACUUUAUAUAUAUUACAAUGAUACAAUGAUUACAUUAACAAUACAAUAUUUUGCUUGUCAUAUGCUAAGAAUAAUUGGGUAGAGUGACAUUACUGUGCCUUCGAUUAAAAUAAGUACUUUUUUGCGUGUUAAAUUCAUGUUUUCAAUAAAUAAUAAAUGCAUAUAGUUGAAAAAUCA